ACAUUUGCCCCUCCUUCCAGACCCUGGCAGCCACCAUUCUACUCUUUGCCUCUAUGAAUUUGACUAUUGUAGAUAGCUCAUGAGUCUCCAUGGGAUACUUGCCUCCGCAGGCACCAUAGGAGCAGUGGCAGCUUGGCUGAUGAGCUAUAAGCCAGCCUUGUUUGGGUUCCUAUUCCUUCUGCUGUUGCUUAGCAACUGGUUGGUCAAGUAUGAACACAAGCUCACCCUCCCAGAGCCCCAGCAGGACGAGAUCCUCCAACGGCUGUUGUUCAGUGAAAUGAAGAUGAAGGUCCUAGAAAAUCAGAUGUUCAUCAUAUGGAAUAAAAUGAAUCACCACGGGCGGUCAAGCAGACAUCGGAAUUUUCCCAUGAAAAAACACAGAAUGAGGAGGCAUGAGUCAAUUUGCCCCACCCUGUCUGACUGUACUUCGAGUUCCCCCAGCUAAUGAGGCCGAGGCGGGCUGGCCUCUGCCGAUGUUACCUUUUACCUCAGUAAAACCCAGUCACAGCCUA